GUCCAUGCUGACCUGAGGAGUCGCGGCUGCGAGCAGGUUCGGUGCUGCGGGUUGGGGUAGGCGGCGGUGGGGUCCCUGGUUCUGGGGCACUGGGAAGAUCGCGAGUCGUGCGUGUGGGAAGGUCCUCCCCCGGUCCUCCGGGUCAUCUUUGCUCCCGAGGAGCGGCAUAUUUCUCAUCUGGCGGAGGUGUCCUGGGGUAGUUGGGUUAGAGUUACUUGUUAUUGGUAAAUAGCCACUAUGGAGGCUAAGGACCAGAAGAAACACAGAAAGAAAAACAGUGGACCCAAAGCUGCAAAGAAAAAGAAGCGGCUUCUGCAGGAUCUCCAGCUAGGAGACGAAGAAGAUGCCCGGAAGAGAAAUCCCAAAGCUUUUGCAGUUCAGUCUGCUGUGCGGAUGGCUCGAUCCUUUCACAGGACUCAGGAUUUGAAGACAAAAAAGCAUCAUAUUCCAGUGGUUGAUCGAACUCCACUAGAGCCCCCACCAAUAGUGGUAGUGGUGAUGGGACCUCCAAAAGUUGGAAAGAGCACUUUGAUACAAUGCCUCAUUCGGAACUUUACCCGGCAGAAGUUGACUGAGAUCAGAGGCCCUGUGACGAUUGUGUCAGGUAAAAAGCGCAGACUCACCAUUAUUGAAUGUGGGUGUGACAUUAACAUGAUGAUUGAUCUGGCUAAAGUAGCAGAUCUGGUACUGAUGCUUAUAGAUGCCAGCUUUGGGUUUGAAAUGGAAACGUUUGAGUUUCUAAACAUCUGUCAAGUACAUGGCUUUCCUAAAAUUAUGGGAGUUCUCACCCACCUCGACUCCUUCAAGCAUAAUAAGCAACUGAAGAAGACAAAGAAGCGAUUAAAACACAGGUUCUGGACGGAAGUUUACCCGGGUGCCAAGCUGUUCUACCUUUCUGGAAUGGUGCAUGGAGAAUAUCAAAACCAAGAAAUCCACAAUCUGGGCCGUUUUAUUACAGUUAUGAAGUUUAGGCCUCUCACAUGGCAAACUUCUCACCCUUAUAUCCUGGCAGACAGGAUGGAAGAUUUGACAAACCCAGAGGAUAUCCGAACAAACAUCAAAUGUGACCGGAAGGUGUCACUUUAUGGUUAUUUAAGAGGAGCACACUUGAAAAAUAAAAGCCAAAUUCACAUGCCAGGGGUAGGAGAUUUUGCCGUGAGUGACAUCAGUUUCCUCCCAGACCCUUGCGCUCUUCCUGAACAACAAAAGAAGCGCUGUUUAAAUGAGAAGGAGAAGCUGGUUUAUGCGCCUCUUUCUGGAGUUGGGGGUGUGCUGUAUGACAAAGACGCUGUCUAUGUUGACCUUGGUGGCAGCCACGUUUUUCAGGAUGAAGUGGGGCCCACCCAUGAGCUGGUCCAGAGUCUCAUCUCUACCCACUCCACCAUUGAUGCCAAGAUGGCUUCAAGUCGAGUGACGCUGUUUUCUGAUUCCAAGCCACUUGGGUCAGAGGAUAUAGAUAAUCAAGGGCUAAUGAUGCCAAAGGAGGAAAAACAAAUGGACUUGAACACUGGUCGAAUGCGUCGGAAAGCCAUUUUCGGAGAUGAAGAUGAAUCUGGAGAUAGUGAUGAUGAAGAAGAUGAUGAAAUGUCUGAAGAUGACGGGUUGGAAAACGGCUCUAGUGAUGAGGAAGCAGAAGAGGAGGAAAAUGCUGAGAUGACUGAUCAGUAUAUGGCUGUUAAGGGCAUCAAACGACGGAAACUUGAGUUGGAAGAAGACAGUGAAAUGGAUUUGCCAGCAUUUGCUGACAGUGACGAUGACCUUGAGAGGAGCUCAGCGGAAGAAGGGGAAGCGGAGGAAGCUGAUGAAAGCAGUGAAGAAGAGGACUGCACUGCAGGAGAGAAGGGCAUUUCAGGAUCAAAGGCUGCUGGAGAAGGUAGUAAAGCAGGGCUGUCACCAGCUAAUUGCCAGAGUGACCGUGUGAAUCUGGAGAAGUCUUUGCUGAUGAAGAAAGCAGCUCUCCCCACUUUCGAUUCUGGGCAUUGCACAGCUGAAGAGGUGUUUGCAUCUGAAGAUGAAUCUGAAGAAAGCUCCUCACUCAGUGCAGAGGAAGAAGACUCAGAAAAUGAAGAGGCUAUUAGAAAAAAGCUUUCAAAGCCUUCUCAAGUGAGCAGUGGUCAGAAACUGGGGCCACAGAACUUCAUUGAUGAGACCAGUGAUAUAGAAAAUUUACUCAAAGAGGAAGAAGAUUACAAGGAAGAAAAUAAUGAUUCCAAAGAAACGUCAGGUGCCCUCAAGUGGAAGGAAGACCUUUCCAGAAAGGCAGCUGAGGCCUUUCUGAGGCAGCAGCAAGCAGCUCCAAACCUCCGAAAGCUUAUUUAUGGGACAGUGACAGAAGAUAAUGAAGAAGAAGAUGAUGAUACUCUAGAAGAGCUUGGAGGGUUGUUUCGUGUCAACCAGCCUGACAGAGAGUGUAAGCACAAGGCUGACUCUUUGGACUGCUCCAGAUUUCUUGUGGAGGCCCCCCAUGACUGGGAUUUAGAGGAGGUUAUGAACAGUAUCAGAGAUUGCUUCGUGACUGGAAAGUGGGAAGAUGAUAAAGAUGCAGCCAAGGUCUUAGCAGAAGAUGAGGAGCUCUACGGUGACUUUGAAGACUUGGAAACAGGGGACGUGCACAAGGGAAAAUCAGGCCCCAAUACUCAGAAUGAAGAUAUAGAGAAAGAAGUUAAGGAAGAAAUUGACCCCGACGAAGAAGAAAGUGCCAAGAAAAAGCAUUUGGAUAAGAAGAGAAAAUUGAAGGAGAUGUUUGAUGCAGAAUAUGAUGAAGGAGAAAGCACAUAUUUUGAUGAUCUUAAAGGAGAAAUGCAGAAACAAGCACAGCUGAAUCGCGCAGAAUUUGAAGAUCAAGAUGAUGAAGCCAGAGUUCAGUAUGAGGGUUUUCGACCUGGGAUGUACGUCCGCAUUGAGAUUGAAAAUGUUCCCUGUGAAUUUGUGCAGAACUUUGACCCCCAUUACCCCAUUAUCCUGGGUGGCUUGGGCAACAGUGAGGGAAAUGUUGGCUACGUGCAGAUGCGUCUGAAGAAACAUCGCUGGUAUAAGAAAAUCCUCAAGUCCCGAGAUCCAAUCAUAUUUUCUGUAGGGUGGAGGAGGUUUCAGACCAUCCCACUGUAUUAUAUCGAAGACCACAAUGGAAGACAAAGGCUUCUAAAGUAUACCCCACAGCACAUGCAUUGCGGAGCAGCCUUUUGGGGCCCUAUCACUCCACAGGGAACUGGUUUCUUGGCAAUACAGUCUGUCAGUGGCAUAAUGCCUGAUUUUCGGAUAGCUGCUACAGGAGUUGUCCUUGAUCUGGAUAAAUCCAUAAAAAUUGUGAAGAAAUUAAAGCUAACUGGUUUUCCAUAUAAAAUUUUCAAGAACACUUCAUUUAUUAAGGGAAUGUUUAAUUCUGCCUUGGAAGUGGCCAAAUUUGAAGGUGCUGUGAUUCGAACAGUCAGUGGGAUAAGGGGGCAGAUCAAGAAAGCACUCCGAGCUCCAGAAGGAGCUUUCAGGGCCAGCUUUGAGGAUAAGCUGCUGAUGAGCGAUAUUGUCUUCAUGCGAACUUGGUAUCCUGUUUCCAUCCCAGCGUUCUAUAACCCAGUAACAUCUUUGUUGAAACCAGUGGGUGAGAAAGACACCUGGUCAGGAAUGCGGACCACGGGCCAACUCAGGCUCGCCCAUGGCGUCAGACUAAAGGCGAACAAGGACUCUCUGUAUAAGCCAAUCCUGAGGCAAAAGAAACAUUUUAAUUCACUGCACAUUCCAAAAGCCUUGCAGAAGGCCCUGCCAUUUAAGAACAAGCCCAAGACCCAAGCAAAGGCAGGCAAGGUGCCAAAGGACAGGCGGAGACCGGCCGUCAUACGCGAGCCUCAUGAAAGAAAGAUCCUUGCACUGCUGGAUGCUCUGAGUACGGUGCAUAGUCAGAAGAUGAAGAAGGCCAAGGAGCAGCGGCACCUGCACAAUAAAGAGCACUUCAGAGCCAAGCAGAAGGAGGAGGAGGAGAAGCUGAAGCGGCAGAAGGACCUCAGGAAGAAGCUCUUCAGAAUUCAGGGGCAGAAGGAAAGAAGAAACCAGAAGUCCAGUUUGAAGGGGGCUGAGGGCCAAUUGCAGUGAGCCUUUGGACUGGAGGGACUGUCCCUGGAUCUGCGGAGGUAGACAGUUUCAAACAUCACAGUUUGAAUGCCUGUGAAUGACAAGUCAGUGGGAAAGAGCUCAAGAGAUGUCUCUACUCAAACUGUGCCUGCAGGAGGAGGAACAGAGAAGCCUGGGCUGCUGGGACUGGGUUCAUUCUCAUGACUUGGGGCUGUCGAGAUUUAAAGUGAUGUAAGCUGUGGUUAUGUGGAUUCUCUUACUUUCCUCUGCCUGCCUCAGUUUAAUUAUUUUGUCCUACAGAAAUAUCAUUAAAAUAUUUUUUUGUUACUUUUGGCUUAGUAGUUUUCAUUAGGGAUGAAUGCCUGACAAUUCUUUGUGGAUAAUUAUUUAUACUACCACCUUCAUGAGGAGUCUUCCAGAAGAGAAAGAAAUAUUCACUUGAACUCUGAGCUCCCAUGGAAGAUUUUAGAGAAUAGUGUGUAGUGUUUUUGUUUUGUUUUUUGUUUGAGUGACACACAAACCUAGAUGGUACAGCCUACUGUGCACCCAGGAUCUAUGGGCUCCUUUGAUCACUGGCCCUUGUGGACAUUUUCUAUCUUAUUUCAUAUGUUCUGCACAUUAGUAUAGUGACAAGGUAACAGUAAGUACUUUUUUAAAGCUUUAGACUUAGGAGAUUAUUGUCUCAGGUGCAGAGACCAAGGAAAUCGUAUGUAUCAGUGAGAUAGGCUUCCCGUAUUAUGCUCAUGCGUUAUACCUGCCUAGCUACAUUGCCUUUUUUUAAAUUAAACAUUAUGUUGAAGUAAUCAUACUAUUACAUAGGCGAUGUAUGUAUUUUAUGAUUGUAUGUUGAUAUAGUUAUGGGGAAUCUAUUCCUAUACGAUGUAAUCAUAGAUUCACAUAUAGUUGUAUAUUUUGCCCAAUUUCUCUCAGUGGUAAUGUUUCACACAUAUAACAAUCAGGAUGUUGACAUCAAUACAGCCCGCUGAUUUUAUUCACAUUUCCCCAGCUUUACUUUCCCCAACGUAUACUCCUCCAUGUAUGCAUGGGUGUGUAGAAAUAUGGAACGCAGCUGGGCACAGUGACUCACGCCUGUAAUCCCAGCACUUUGGGAUGCUAAGGCAGGAGGAUCACUUGAGCCCAGGAAUUUGAGACCAACUUGGGCAACAUGGCAAAACCUCAUCGCUACAAAAAAUAAAAAAUUCGCCAGGUGUGGUGGGUGCACACCUGUAGUUCCAGCUGCUUGGGAGGCUGAGGUAGGAGGAUCACUUGAGCUUGGGAGGUUGAGGCUGCAGUGAGCCAUGAUAGCACCACUGCACUCCAGCCUGGGCGACAGGGCAAGACCCUGUUUCAAAAAAAAAAAAUUAUACAUAUAUGUAUGUAGAACACUUCAUGAAUUUGUGUGUCAUCUGUGCAUGGGGCCCAUGCUGACCUCUGUGUUGUGCCAGUUAUAGUAUGUGUGCUGCUGAUAUGAGUGCCACAUUGCCUUUACAACAUCAUAGGGGCCAAAGAGGGUUGGCAGGAUUAUGAGCAGUUGGCCUAGUCUGAGAGGCUCUCUAAAAGCCUAAAGUCUGUAGGCAGGUGCUCAGCUUUGUAUCUCCAUAAGAAGGGAAGAGGAUGUGAGGAUCCUGUCAGGGCUAGGUCCACCUGGGAAGUGACAAUUGGAACACUCCCAGACCUCUCUGGGCAACUCUGGGUGUACAUUUUCCUCUGUUCCUCAAGAGCUAUUAUGAAUUUCAUCAUCCAUUAUGCUGAUAGGCCUGGGGACUGACACAUAGUAAGCCCAUAACAAUUAUAAUUUAAAACUAAUUUGUUAUAUAGCAUAAUUGAUAUAUUUUAAAAUGCAAAACUAUAAUUCAACUAAAAUAUACAAGGCACUCAAGUCAUACCAUGUUUUAAGUAGCUUACAAGGUGAUCAGCAAGUGUCUUAUACAACAAGCAAAUUUGUUCAAAGAGAAGCAUUGCAAAUAAGUAUUUAUAAUUGUAUAGUUUUAUAUUUUAGCCAGAAGAGUGGAAUCCUUUAGCAAUGGGGGAAAUAAAAGAAUGUUUAAUUACAGUUGCAGAUAAUUGCCUUUUCCAAAGACAAUGUAUGUAGGCAGAACUCAUACCUGUUAAUAUUAAAAAUCUUGGUUUAUCAUAUUUGGAGAACAAGGGAAAUAAAAAGUUUGCAUAUUAAGAUUAUUUAAACUAAAGUUAAGGAAUCUCUAAUGUCUGAAAGAAACAAUAAAUAGCAUUUUUCAUGUAGAAUUUUUAUUGGUGAAGGUUCCACCUGGCCAGGUUAGUAAAAUACAGUCACACAUCAGUUAAGGAUGGGGAUAUAUUCUGAGAAAUGUAUCAUUAGGCAAUUUUGUCAUUGUGUAAACAUCAUAGAGUGACACACAAACCUAGAUGGUACAGCCUACUGUGCACCUGGGCUCUAUGGUAUGGCCUGUUGCUCCUAGGCUACAAACCUGGGCAGCAUGUGACUGUACUGACUACUGUAGGCAGUUGUAACACAGUGGUAAACAUUUGUGUAUCGAAACAUAGAAAAGGCGUAGCAAAAAUACAGUAUUGUGGAACCACUGCCAUAUACGUGGUCCAUCCUUGACUGAACAUCAUGCGGCAUGUGGCUGUAUGUAUACACAUAGUUUUUGCUGUGAGUUUGCAUCCAUCUCAUAGGAAGACAUAUAUCAAAAUAAGGACCAGACUGGAGAGUGUGUAAAUUACUUUUCAAUACUAAUGGCUUAUUAAUUUGAUAUUGUCAGCAAGUAUGUUGCAAAAACAAAUUCCACCAGAAUGUGAGUUCCAUGAGAGCAGGAACUGGGUUGUUCACCUUGUUGGCACUUGGAGUAGAGCCACUGAGCUUCGUGCUGCAUAAAAUUGCUUGGAAGAAAGAAGGGAGGGCAUUCCAGGUAACUGAAGCAUUGCUAUGCAAAGUAAGCAUUUGCCCUCUGAAAUAUUUUAACAAUGUUUAUAGAAACCUUUCUCAAUUGUAUUAAACUUUGUAAAUUGUAAAAAUUAUUCUGUUAUACCUUUUCUAUUUACUAGGCACAGGCAGCCAUAGGUGCUAGGUAUGUUUUGAAAACAUAUUGAACCUACAGUGUACAUAUCAUUCCAUGCCAUUAAAUAUUCUUAUUUAAUCAUAGAUGUGUUCAGGUGUGUUUGGUUUCCUAUUUGUGGAUGUACUAGAUUGUUUUCUUUUUUUAACAAAACCUGUGAACUUGCUUUAAGUAUUAUCAUUUGGUGACAUGCCCGCCAUUUCAGAAAUAAAUGUUUGAGCAAAGAGGAAAGCCACCGGGUCUGAUUCAGCUCUCUGGAGGCUCCAGAGCUUACCUCGCUGAUGGGAAAAAGAGCAUCGAUUUAAUUGCCCUUGGUACCGACUUCUAGUAUCUAGUAUUUUGCCAGACUCAGGUAUUUCUUAAAGCCAUUAUUCAGAGUCUUCAGCAAGGACAUUGUAUUUUACUUGUGUCUCCUUAGUUUUACCUAGUUUAUUUCAUGGUUUUAAAGUAUUGUACAUUUUUAUAAUCCUUUAACAAGACAAAAGGUUGAGAUGUUGGACAUUUAAAUGCCAAAGGUGUUUUAUUAUGAGACUUAGCAUUUCAUAUUUGGGGAUGGUACCUUAUCGAAAAUCAGAUAAACUUUGGUUGGAUGGGUAUUUGGAGGAAUCUUUUAAGUCUUUUCUUAAGCAAAGUUUGGACACUCUAAAAUAAGGUUGCCAACUGGCAUGUAGAGAGAAAAGGAUGUGUCAUACAUUUAGACCAGGUGGCCUGUCCUGUAAAUUUUUUUGAGGGGAGGGGUGGGCUUGUUUUUUUCUGUGUUUCGGUUUUUUCCAAUUUUUGUUUUGUGAUAAAAUAUGCAUAAUAAAACUUAUUUUAUCAAUUUUUAA